AUCCUUAGAUUCGCUCCUCCGGGCAGGGAGCGGAGACGGAGGAGGAGGAGGGAGAGGCUGAAUGUUGGCUCGGUAAUUGAGAGGAGCGGCCGCUCCAGAGCUUCCUCCCGGGGCGCCCCCCUCAGUCCGUCCGCGCUUCUCAGCCGCCAGUCUCCUGGCCGCGCAGUCCCCGCGGACGGCCGGGCCGCGGAGACCCUCGCAGAAGAGGCGCUGCCGGCGGCGAGGACUGGCCGGCGGCAUCCGAGGCGCGCGCCCCACCGCCACCCCCACCCGCCUGCCAGCCGGUCCCUCCGGCCGCCGCCAUGUCCUCCUCCUCUUCCUCCCCCAGGGAGACGUACGAGGAGGACCGGGAGUACGAGAGCCAGGCCAAGCGUCUCAAGACCGAGGAGGGGGAGAUCGACUACUCGGCCGAGGAAGGCGAGAACCGCCGGGAAGCGACGCCCCGGGGCGGGGGCGAUGGCGGCGGCGGCGGCCGGAGCUUCUCUCAGCCGGAGGCAGGUGGAAGUCAUCAUAAAGUUUCUGUUUCACCCGUCGUCCAUGUUCGAGGACUCUGUGAAUCUGUGGUGGAAGCAGACCUCGUGGAAGCGCUGGAAAAAUUUGGGACAAUAUGCUAUGUGAUGAUGAUGCCAUUUAAACGACAGGCUCUAGUGGAAUUUGAAAACAUAGAUAGUGCCAAAGAAUGUGUGACAUUUGCUGCAGAUGAACCCGUGUACAUUGCUGGUCAACAGGCUUUUUUCAACUAUUCUACAAGCAAAAGGAUCACUCGGCCAGGAAAUACUGAUGAUCCAUCAGGAGGCAACAAAGUUCUUCUGCUCUCAAUUCAGAAUCCGCUUUAUCCAAUUACAGUGGAUGUUUUAUAUACUGUAUGCAACCCUGUUGGCAAAGUGCAACGUAUUGUUAUAUUCAAGAGAAAUGGGAUACAAGCAAUGGUUGAGUUUGAAUCAGUCCUUUGUGCCCAGAAAGCUAAAGCAGCACUCAAUGGAGCUGAUAUAUAUGCUGGAUGUUGCACACUAAAAAUUGAAUAUGCACGGCCAACUCGUCUAAAUGUUAUUAGGAAUGACAAUGACAGUUGGGACUACACUAAACCAUAUUUGGGAAGACGAGAUAGAGGAAAGGGUCGCCAGAGACAAGCCAUUUUGGGAGAACACCCUUCUUCGUUUAGACAUGAUGGCUAUGGAUCCCAUGGUCCAUUAUUGCCUUUACCAAGUCGUUACAGAAUGGGCUCUCGAGAUACACCUGAACUUGUUGCUUAUCCAUUACCACAGGCUUCUUCCUCUUACAUGCAUGGAGGAAAUCCCUCUGGUUCAGUUGUAAUGGUUAGUGGAUUACAUCAACUAAAAAUGAAUUGUUCAAGAGUCUUCAACCUGUUCUGCUUAUAUGGAAAUAUUGAGAAGGUAAAAUUUAUGAAGACCAUUCCUGGUACAGCACUGGUAGAAAUGGGUGAUGAGUAUGCUGUAGAAAGAGCUGUCACACACCUUAAUAAUGUCAAAUUAUUUGGGAAAAGACUUAAUGUUUGCGUGUCUAAACAACAUUCAGUUGUUCCAAGUCAAAUAUUUGAGCUGGAGGAUGGUACCAGCAGCUACAAAGAUUUUGCAAUGAGCAAAAAUAAUCGCUUUACAAGUGCUGGCCAAGCAUCUAAGAAUAUAAUCCAGCCACCCUCCUGUGUUUUGCAUUAUUAUAAUGUUCCAUUGUGUGUCACAGAAGAGACCUUCACAAAGUUGUGUAAUGACCAUGAAGUUCUUACAUUCAUCAAAUAUAAAGUGUUUGAUGCAAAACCUUCAGCCAAAACACUUUCUGGGCUAUUAGAAUGGGAGUGCAAAACUGAUGCAGUAGAAGCCCUUACGGCACUGAAUCACUAUCAGAUAAGAGUGCCGAAGACGGGGUUUCACCACGUUGGCCAGGCUGGUCUCGAACUCCUGGACCUCAUGAUCUGCCCACCUCCGCCUUCCGAAGUGCUGGGAUUACAGGCAUGGUUCCAAUCCCUAUACAUUGAAGCUUUGCUUUUCUACAUCAUCCCAUUUAUAAGAAGAGAAGAGCAUGUUAGAAUUUAUGUUCACCUUUAUUACAAUUUCAAAGCUACACUUCAUUAAAAAAAAAUCUAAAAUGGUUGAUCUCAUGUUGCCUUGCUUACUUUAAGAUCCUGUUCUGUAAUAAACAUAUUUUGCCUUGAGUAAAUUUGUUGUAAGCUUAAAUAUUGAAUUGUUUUCAUUUUAAGAUAGAAUAUCAUAAUGUAGACUAUCUACAGCUUCAUUGUAGAUUAUACAGAUAUAUGAUUUCUAACCUUAUUACUGGAAUUUUUCUUCCACAGUAAAAAUAUAUUUGCAUUCUUAAUGCUAAUUAUCUGCAAGUAUUUUUUCAUUGUGUAAGAGAUUAAUGCAGGUGAAAGUAUUGCAUUUUAAUAUAGAAUUCCUAUUAUAUGUUUAGAUGUUUAAGUAUGUUGCAGUUACUCAUAUUAAACAUAACUUGUAUAUUUAUUAUUUUAAUGAAGUUUGAGAAUAACGUUACAUAUGUUGAAUUUUAAGUACUACAGAUUUAACUGAUUUUAUAUUUCUGAAAGGCUAACAGACAUGGAUACACGUGUACAGUAUGCAUUCAAACUUAUUUAAAUUGGUGUAUUUUUUUUUAAGUCACUGUCCAUUUGUAUUGACAUGCCUCUGUUUCUAGUCCAGUUUGGAGAUUUUAUAAAGUUAUAACAAUGAGUUAAUGUGUUCAUUUUCAUUUGUUGCAUGUGACUUAAAUACAGCUAGUAUUUGGCAUUGAGAUUUUAAUAGAGGUUAUAAUUAACAGUUCCUCUUAUAGAUAAUAAUCUGGGAUCCAUGGGUGGGCUUCAGAGAAUCUGUGUACCCCCUAAAAUUGUAUGUAGAAUUUUGGAUAUUUACAUUUUUAUUUUUUAACUCUUGGAUCCAUCAGUAAUAUGUAUUUUUCUAUAUGGUACAAGAUUUAAGGAUCUAAUUUUAUUUUUAUUCCAAACAGAUAGCUAUUUGUCUCAAUACCAUUUAUUAAACAUUCUUUCUCCCACUGGAUCUGUUUUUUUUUUCUUUUUAAGAUAAUAGAUUUUAUACAUAGGCAAGUAAGAUUUAAGGACCAAACAUGGUAUUAAGAGACUAUAGCACGAUUGUUACCAAGUUCACAGCUUUUUUACAAUAGAAAAACUGAUGUGGCCAUUUUGUUUUCAUCUUUAAAAGAAGGGAGAAUAUGUGUCAUCUACCUAGAAUAACUGAUAUCAGUAGUUGACAAUAUCAGUUUUGUAAUCCUGACACUUUUAAACAAAUUUGUAAAUGAAAGUUCCAUUUAGAUCUUUUGUAAAGACUUUAUUUUAAAUUUUAAUAUAAAAAAUCCUUUUAGAAAUAAGGCAGGCAUUUACAAUUUUAGAGCUGUUUAAUAGGAAGUUUAGAUGGAAACUAAACACACAUUAACAUUUAUUUCCCCUCAUUUUGAUGGCAGUGGACCAGCAUUUAGCCCUCUAAAGAUAAAGAAAAAAUUAAAUUUAAUCUAGAAGUAUUUUAGACCCUUAUCACAGAACCCAGUAAGUUAUGCCAAGGGUAACUGUGUGAACUGUGUUCGAUACUGGGCUAUGUAUGUUUCUUAUUCAUUGCCAAUUUAAUACCUAAGUUUAUCUAACUUUACAAUAAAGCUUUUUUUCCCCUAUAAAUACUUUUCUACCUCUUUUGAAAAAUUGAAAUACCUUAAUUUUGGUUUAUGUAAUAGUUGUCUACGUUCCUUCCUCCUCUGAAAAUUAAUGUGGGUUGUCAGAAUUACAGACUUUUUAAUGCCUAAGAUUUUAAGAAAUAAACCUGUAGGUGUUGGCAGGACUUAUUUCAUUUAGAUUUUAAUUAGUUUAGAUGUGUAGAAAUGAUUUUUAUCUGUAAGGCUCUCUCUCCACCAAAAUAAGUGAAUUGUUUGGGAGUAAACUAGUUGGUAAGUUGGGCCUUGCUGAUAGAUUUAUACACUGGUGUGUAAGCCCUAUACUGCUGCUGUCACUAAUGUUUUUGAUAGUUUACUUAGGCAUGACUGCUGUUAAUGAAGUUUGCUUUGUGAAUACUCUCUCUUUCCUUAGCCUUGGCAACAUUCUUCUCUGUGCUAUCUUUAUGCUUUUAGAAGAACUAGAAAAAGCAGAUUUAAGAACUGUAAAGAAAUAAUACUAGCUUUGAGUUUUUAAAAAAAAUAUUGAAAUCCCAUCUCUGUAUCCAAAUCCUACUACACAUUUGAUAAUAAAUCUGCCAAACUGAGUUAUGGAA